CCACAAGAUUGAGAAAUGGAAAAGUGUUUUUUUAAACACACCUUUCUUAUCAGUUUGCUAGAUUAGCAGGCCCGAGUGAAUGCAGUUAAGUUAAUAAAGUAUAAAAUUGAAAAUAAAGCUCAUCAAAGCAUAAUCAGCUAGUUUGAUAUCUGUAAAUAGAUGUAGCCGUCUCACCACUAUAAUGGUACUAUAAUAAUUGACAUAAAAGUGGAUUAUAUGAUUUACUCUAUGCUUAAAUUAUUUGGACUUUAAUAUUUUAUUAAUACAUUUAUUGGCAUUAAAAAGCACUGUGUAGAAUGAGGCAACUGCUCUAGGUAAAUAAUAAUUUAGUCAACAUGUUAUGUUUAUAAUGUAUCAUUGCAUGUCACUAUUUUAAAAAUAUUUAUACAGCUUCUUAAAUGUAUGAAGUAAGCAAUGUGAGACAUAGUACGAUAUGGUUUGGCUGUGUUGUAGGAGGGACUGGUGGGAGGUAAUUGAAUCAUGGGGGCAGGUCUUUCCCAUGCUGUUCUCGUGAUAGUGAACGGUUUUUUAAAGAGGAGUUCUCCUGUACAAGCUCUUUUUGCCUGCCGCCAUCCACAUAAGAUGUGACUUGCUCCUCUUUGCCUUCCACCAGCAUUGUGAGGCCUCCUCAGCCAUGUGGAACUGUGAGUCCAAUUGAACCUUUUUUUUUUGUAAAGUGCCCAGUCUCGGGUAUGUCUUUAUCAGCAGGAUGAAAACAGACUAAUACAGCAAAUUAGUACAAGUAGAGUGGGGCAUUGCUCAAAAGAUACCUGAAAAUGUGGAAGUGACUUUGAAACUGGGUAACAGGCAGAGGUUGGAACAAUUUGGAUGGCUCAGAAGAAGAUAGGAAAAUGUGGGAAAUUUGGAACUCCCUAGAGACUUGCUGAAUGGCUUUGACAAAAAUGCUGAUAGUGAUAUGAGCAAUAAGGUCCAGGCUGAGGUAGUCUCAGAUGGAGAUGAGGAACUUGUUGGGAACUGGAGCAAAGGUGACUCUUGUUAUGUUUUAGCAAACAGACUGUCAGCAUUUUGACCCUGCCUUAGAGAUUUGUGGAACUUUGAACUUGAGAGAGGUGAUUAGGGUGUUUGGCGGAAGAAAUUUCUAAGCAGCAAAGAAUUCAAGAGGUGGCUUGGGUGCUGUUAAAGGCAUUCAGUUUUAUAAGGGAAGCAGAGCAUAUAAGUUCAGAAAAUUUGCAGCCUGACAAUACCACAGAAAAGAAAAACCCAUUUUCUGAGGGGAAAUGCAAGCCAGCUGCAGAAAUUUGCAUCAGUAACAAGGAGCCAAAAGUUACUCAUCAAGACAAUGGGGAAAAUGUCUCCAGGGCAUAUCAGAGACCUUUGUGGCAGCCGCUCCCAUCACAGACCUGGAGGUUUAGGAGGAAAAAUUGGUUUCAUGGGUCCGUCCCAGGGUCCCUUUGCUGUGUGCAGUCUAGGGACUUGGUGCCCUGCAUCCCAGCCACUUCAGCUGUGACUAAAAGGGGCCAAGGUAUAUCUCAGGCUGUGGCUUCAGAGGGUGUAAGCCCCAAGCCUUGGCAGCUUCUAUGUGGUGUUGAGCCUGCGAGUGCACAGAAGUCAAGAAUUGGGGUUUGGGAACCUCUGCCUAGAUUUCAGAGGAUGUAUGGAAAUGCCUGGAUGCCCAUGCAGAAGUUUGCUGCAGGGAUGGGGCCCACAUGGAGAACCUCUGCUAGGGCAGUGUGGAAAGGAAAUGUGAGGUUGGAGCCCCCACACAGAAUCCCUGCUGGGGCACCACCUAGUGGAGCCAUGAGAAGAGGGCCACUGUCCUCCAGACCCCAGAAGGGUAGAUCCACCAGCAGCUUGCACUGUGCGCCUGGAAAAACUGCAAACAUUCAAUGCCAGCCCGUGAAAGCAGCCAGGAGGGAGGCUGUACCCUGCAAAGCCACAGGGGCAGAGCUGCCCAAGACCAUGGGAACCCACCUCUUGCAUCAGUGUGACCUGUAUGUGAGACAUGGAGUCAGAGGAGAUAAUUUUAGAGCUUUAAGAUUUGAUGGCACUGCCAGAUUCUGAACUUGUGUGGGGCCUGCAGCCCCUUUGUUUUGACCAAUUUCUCCCAUUUGGAAUGGCUGUAUUUACCCAAUGCCUGUACCCUCACUGUAUCUAGGAAGUAACUAACUUGCUUUUGAUUUUACAGGCUCGUGGGCAGGUCUCAGAUGAGACUGGACUGUGGACUUUUGAGUUAAUGCUGAAAUGAAUUAAGACCUUGGGGGACUGUUGGGAAGGCAUGACUGGUUUUGAAAUGUGAGGACAUGAGAUUUGGGAGGGACUGGGGCAGAAUGAUAUGGUUUGGCUGUGUCCCCCUAAAUCUCAUCUUGAAUUCCCAGUGUUGUAGGAGGGACAGGUGGGAGGUAAUUGAAUCAUGGGGGCAGGUCUUUCCUGUGCUGUUCUAGUGAUAGUGAAUAAGUCUCAUGCGAUCUGAUACUUUUAUAAAGAGAAGUUCCCCUGCACAAGCUGUUUUUGUCUGCCACCCUCCACGUAAGGUGUGACUUACUCCUCCUUGCCUUGCACCAUGAUUGUGAGGCCUCCCCAGCCAUGUGGAACUGUGAGUCCAGUUAAACCUCUUUCUUUUUUAGAUUGUCCAGUCUUAGGUAUGUUUUUAUCAGCAGUGUGAAAACAGACUAACAUGGUGUCUCAGAGGAUAAGGACAACAAUUCUGUAAAUUUUUGUUAAUUUAGUGAGUAGGCCUACAUGUAAAAAAGCUGUUUUAAAAUUAAAUAUGACUUUAAUUUUAAAAAUUAAACAUUUUUGCAUUAUCAAAGUUAAAUAUACACCAUGGAAAUUUGAAUAACUAGAAGAAGGGAGAAAACACCUUUUCUAACGUUUAUCAUUAGUGUCAUAUUUUAUUGAUUCUAAGAUGCACUUUUUUUACAUUUUAGCAUCUCUGUUCACAUUUUAACUUCUCUGAAAUUUGGAUGCAACUUACAAUGAUGGCAUUUAGCUAAAAUCAUAUUAGCAUAUUGGUGCAUUUCCUUUUUACUAUGCAUACUUUUAUCUUGCCUAUAAAAAUACUGCAUAUCAGCUUGCAUGAAAGUCAAACUUCUGACUAUAAAUUCAUUGUUGUUGCCAUUCUUUAGUUUAUCUUGGAGGUGUGGCUAAAAAAGGUAAAAAUAUGCGAAAAAGAAGAAUUUGAGAUAAAAUCAGAUUUUUUCCUCUUUCCAGAAUGAGGGCUGGAGGAAGUAGCUUGGCCUGAGAUAGGCAGGUAGAAAUCAAUCAACUACUCAAAAACAAAGAACCCAAAGAUCAUGCCACCAAGUCAAAGUCGAGUGCUUGCUAUGUACCAGAUGCUGGGUUUUCAGAUGUUAAGCUAAAAAGUAAAUUAGACAAGAGUUUUGCUGUUAAGAAACUCAUAGACUAUUGAAAGAGAGAAUGUUGUAUCUUGACAUUUUAUAUGAAAUUUCUAGUUCAAAAAAAACCAACAAACAUUCCCUGAUAAUAUUUUAUUUAAAAUAUGGUUUGUUGUUGCUUUUUGAGACAGACUCACUCUGUGGCCUGGGCUGGAGUACAUGGUGCCAUCAUGGCUCACUGCAGCCUUGACUUCCUGGGCUCAAUUGAUCCUCCCACCUCAGCCUCCUGAGUAGCUGGGACUAUAGGUGUGCACCACCAUGCCUGGCUAAUUUUUAAUUUUUUUGUAGAGAUAGGGUCCCAAAGUGUUAGGACGAUAUAGGCGUGAACCACCAUGCCUGGACUAAAAUAUAGUUCUUUAUUUACCUGUGAAUACAGUUAUGUUGCAUCAGGAAAUUAGAUUUAAGAUAUUUUCAACUGUAGGACUCGUGACUUUUUACCCCAUCAACAGUGCCCAAGAUAUAUUGUUUAGUAAAGAGGUGGGGUGGAGGAAGCAAGCAUGGGACAGAAUAAAUGAGGUGAUCCCAUUUCUUAAGUAUCAUAUAAUUUCUAAUUUAACUGUUACUGGUUGAAUACAUUUCUGUAUGUAUUUUAUGACUGGUUCAAGAAAAUAUCUAUUCUCUCUUCCCCCACUGGAGGAAACAGGAAUGUGAGAGGAAAUAACAACAUUUAUCCAGUACGUUCUGUUGAGCGCUAUAUGUCAAUAGGCUAGGCUUUGAGAUACCAAAUUAAAUAAACGUUAUUUUUAACUCCAGUCUUGUGGCACUAUUACUACAAAUGCAUAGAAAAUUUGUACAACUGAGUAUGAGUAGACCUGUGGUAGUAACACAGUUUAAUUCUUCUGGUUGUUACCUGGGAGGGUUUCAUACUGGAGCUUGACCUUAAGAAAUAUAUAGUGUUUUGCUAAGGGGUAAAAGGCAUUCCAGGUAGGGAAAACAGCUUGCACAAAGGCAUGGAGUUAAUGGAGUUAUAUUUGAGAAGGAACUGCAAGGAGACGAAGCUGGAGAUAUUACUAUAAAUAAAGUAUUUAUUGAACACUUAACCAUAUUUUAGACAUUGUUCUAAAUGUUUUACGUUUAUUCCUAACAACAGUCUUUUGAAAUAAUUCUUUUUAUUGUCUUCAUUUUACAGGUGAGGAAUAAGUAAAAAUGGUAUCUAAUUAUGAGAGUCCUUAAGUUCGAAUUAACCAUGUGGAAGGUAAAAGGCAGAAUAAAACAUUUAAAUCAAAGUCUUUCAAAUGAAUUUAGAUUCAAAGAACUCAAGAAUCAUUCAGGGGUUAAAAAAGGUUUUAUAUUAAAUUACAAAGUGAAAUUCAUUAUUAAAAUUCUAUUUGCUAUAUUAAGUCAUGCAUUGCUUAACAAUGGAGAUGUCUUCUGAGAAAUGCACUGUUAGGCAAAUUUUUUUUCUUUUUUUUUUUGAGACGGAGUCUCACUCUGUUGCUCAGACUGGAGUGCAGUGGCACUAUCUCGGCUCACUGCAACCUCUGCCUCCUGGGUUCAAGCAAUUCUCCUGCCUCAGCCUCCUGAGUAACUGGUAUUACAGGCACGCACCACCACCAUGCCCGGCUAAUUUUUGUAUUUUCAGUAGAGACAAGGUUUCACCCUGUUGGUCAGGCUGGUCUCGAAUUCCUGACCUCGUGAUCCACCCACCUCGGCCUCCCAAAGUGCUGGGAUUACAGGCGUAAGCCACAACGCCCAGCCUUUUUUUUUUUUUUUCCAGACAUAGUUUCGCUCUUGUUGCCCAGUGUGGAAUGCAGUGGCCCGAUCUCGGCUCACUGCAACCUCUACCUCCCGAGUUCAAGCGAUUCUCCUGCCUCAGCCUCCUGAGUAGCUGGGAUUACAGGCAUGUGCCACCAUGAGCAGCUAAUUUGGUAUUUUUAGUACAGACGGGAUUUCUCCAUUUUGGCUAGGCUGGUCUGAAACUCCUGACCUCAGGUGAUCUGCCUGCCUUGGCCUCCCAAAGUGCUGGGAUUACAGGUGUGAGCCACCACGCCCGGCCCGGUUAGGCAAUUUUAUUGUUGUGUGAACAUCAUAGAGUGCACUUAUACAAACAUAGAUGCUAUAUACACACCCAAGCUGUAUGGUAUAUGGUAUAGUCUAUUGCUCCUAGGCUACAAACCUGUACCUCAUGUUACUGUACUGAAUACUAUAGGCAGUUGUAACACAAUGGUCAGUUUUUUUUUUUUUUUUGUCUAAACAUGUCUUUUUUUUAGACAGUGUCUGGAUCUGUCGCCUAGGCUUUAGUGCAGCAGCAUAGUCUUGGCUUACUGCAACCUCCGCCUCCCAGGUGCAAGUGCUUCUCCUGCCUCAGCCUCCCCUGUAGCUGGGACUACAGGUGUGGGCCAUCAUGCCCUGCUAAUUUUUUUUUUUUUCCAGUUAAAACGGGGUUUUGCCAUGUUGGCCAGGCUAGUCUCGAACUCCUGGCCUCAAGUGAUCUGCCCACUUUGGCCUCCCAAAGUGCUGGGAUUAUGGGUAUGAGCCACUGCUCCCAGCCUCUAAACAUGUCUUAACAUAGAAAAGGUUCAGUUAAAAUAUGGCAUAAAAGAUCAAAAACGGUGUACCUGUAUAAGGUGUAGUUACCAUGAAUGGAGCUUGCAGGACUGGAAGUUGCUGUGGGUGAAUCAUUGAGUGAGUUAUGAGUGAAUGUGAAGGCCUAGCAUAUUAUUGCACAUGACUGUAGACUUUAUAAACACUGUACACUUAGGCUACAUGAAAUUUAUUUAAAAAAAAUUUUUUAGUUUAAAAAAAAUCACUGUCUUCCACUUCUAUAUCUUGUCCCACUGGAAGGUCUUCAGGGACAGUAAAAUGUGUGGAGCUGUCAUUCAUAUGAUAGCAGUACCUUCUUCUGGAAUACUUUUUGAAGGAUCUGCUUGAGGCUGUUUUAUAGUUAACUUUUUUUUUAAGUAGGAGUACACUCUAAUAUAAUGAUGAAAGUAUAGUAUAGUAAAUACAUAAACAAGUAACAUAGUCAUUUAUUAUUAUUAUCAAGCAUUAAGUACUGUACCUAAUUGUUUUAUAUGACUGGCAGUGCAGCAGUAGUUUCAUCACCACAUACAUGUGAGUAAUGUGUUGUACUGCGGUAUGAUGUCAGCUACAGAGUCACUAGGUGAUAGGAAUUUUUCAGCUCCAUUAUAAUCUUAUGGGACCACUGUUGUGUAUGCAUUUUUCACUGAAAUGUUAUGCAGUACAUGAGUGUAAUACAAUCAUGGUGCAAUACUCUAAGAGUUAAGGCACCUUUUAUUGUAGAUUAUACCACAGACAGAAAACUGCAUAAAUACAUAAAUAAUGCAAUGACAUCUUUUACAAAACAAAACACCCUUUUAACCACUACCCAGAUCAAGAAAUAAAUCUUUGCCAGCCACUGCAGAAGCCUUCCACAUGGCCCUUCCCAGUCACAGCCCCUUUCCUCUCACCUAAAAGUAAUUGCUAUCCUGACUUCUGUAUAAUCGCAUCUUUGUGUUUCCUAUAAUUUCAUCACCCAAAUGUGCAUUCCUGAAAACUAUAAUUUAGUUGUGUUUGUGGUUUUUUUUUUAUCUAUGUCUCUUAACCUACAUAUCCCCCUGCCACCUCCCUUUCCCUUUCUUUCUUACAGUUUAUUCCCUGAAGCAGCCAGUUAUUUUGACCUGUACAGAUUCUGUAGUCUAGAUUAUGCUGAUUGCAUACUUUUUCUUCAUCCUUUGUAUUUCCCAUAAAUUGGUAGUUGGAUCUAAAACCUUGAUCAAAUUUAGGUUUUGCUUUGAGUUUUGUUUUUUUUCCACUUCCUAGGAGUUAGUGUGGUAUAUUCACCAUCAGGAGAUAUAUAAAGCCAGGCAUGGUGGUUCUCACCUGUAAUCCCAGCACUUUGGGAGGCCCAGGCAGGAGGAUAACUUGAGCCCAGGAGUUUGAGACCAGUCUGGGCAACGUAAUGAGACCCUGUGUCUAUAAAAAGUAAAAAACAUUAGGGAGGUGUGGUGGUACAUGCCUGUAAUUCCAGCUACUGAGGUGGGAGGAUCACUUCAGCCUAGGAGAUUGAGUCUGCAGUGAACUGUGAUGGCACCAUGCAUUCCAGCCUGGGCAACAGAGCAAGAUUCUGUCUUGCAAAAAAGAGAGUUAUAGUGUCUAGUUUUCUCUCUUUUUGUGAUUUUAGCAGCCACUGAUGCUUGACACCUAGAUCAGUGAAUUUAUUAAAGCUUGCAAUAUGGUGAUAUUUGAAUUCUGUUAUUUCUUCACUUAUAAGGUGGAAUGCUUCCACAGAAAGAAACCUUUUCUUUUCUGCUAUCUGGUUAGUAGUUGUACCUAGUGGUGCAGUUCAAUUAGGAAAAGUUGGAUAUUUGCUUCUUCAUUUACCAGUUAUCAAAAUAAUAUGUUAAUUUCGUGUUAUUACCUAAAAGUGACCAGUGAGUUCUUCUUGUCAUUAUGAACCUUUUGAUUUAAUUAUUUGUGCUUCAGUUUAUUACAGCUCUUGUCCUUAUUUUUGCUCAAUUGUCCCAUCUUGGACCAAUGGGAGCCUCUUUAAGCUGGCUCCUUAGUGCUUUUGACAUGGCUUUAGUGAUCUUUGAUAGCUUCCUUGCUGUCUGUAGUAAUAUGUUCCAGGCUCCUCUUAGACAUUUCCUGACCCAGAUCUAGAAUCAGCUUUUUUUCCUAAGAAGAGGUUGCUUCCUUUUAUUGGGAAAUGGUAUUUCAAGAUCACAAUUGGAAUUUAGGGAUGCUCAUUGCUACUAGGUUGGCAGUUGUUUCUAGGCUUUUCUUAUGGACAGAGCCACGAUAUGCAUACUGACACUUCCAAUCCACAUACAAGAUUUCAAGAUUUUUUAAAUUAUCAUCUUCUAUUUACAUCUGUAUCUCCUUGUAUCCCAAACUGAUAAUCCUGAUUCUCAAAGACACAGUUGAUGGUCAAAUUAGAGUAUCACGGAAAUAUUCAGUUGCGUUAUCCCACUUUACACACUCAGUGUUCUCCAAAUAAUAAUACAAAUAUCUCUACUAUUAAUAUGAUUACUGAAAAUAGUUAAAUUUUUUUCACAUAGGCUCUUUCCAUUCUUCCUUAUUUUUUGGUUGUACUGUAUCUGUGUUGUCAGAGCAUAUUGAUAUAGGCAUGCCUCAUUUUAUUGCACUUUACUUUUUUGUGCUUUGGCGGUAAUGUGUUUUUUACAAAUUGAAAGUUUGUGGCAACCCUGCAUUGAGCAAGUCUAUUGAAGCCAUUUUACCAACAGCAUGUGCUCACUUCAUGUCUCUGUAUCAUAUUAUGGUAAUUCUCGUGAUAUUUCAAACUUUUUCAUUUAUCAUAUCUGUUAUGAUGAUCUGUGAUUGGACAUCUUUGUUGUUACUAUUGUAAUUGUUUUGGGGUGCCAUGAAAUUCAAAAGCUAGGUUUCUUGUGCCAGUUAGCCAAGUUGUGAAUGCAAAGGAAAAGUUCUUGAAGGAAAACUGCUCCUUCAGUAAACACAAGAAUGAUAAGAAACAGCCUUAUUGCUGAUAGGGAGAAAGUUUGAGUGGUCUGGAUAGAAGAUCAAACCAGCUGCAACAUUCCCUUAAGCUAAAACCUAAUCCAGAGCAAGAUCCUAACUCUUCAGUUCUGUGAAGGCUGAGAGAGGUGAGGAAGCUGUAGAAGAAAAGUUUGAGAUUAGCAAAGGUUGGUUCAUGAGGUUUAAGGAAAGCAGCCAUCUCUAUAAUAUGAAAUUGCGAGGUGAAACAGCAAGUACUGAUGUGGAAGCUACAGCAAGUUAUCCAGAAGAUCUAGCUAAGAUAAUCGAUAAAGGUGGACUAUACUAAACUACAGGUUUUCAAUGUAGACAAAACAGCUAUCUAUUGGAGAAGAUGCCACCUAGGACUUUCAUAGCUAGAGAAGAUAAGUAAAUGCCUUGCUUCAAAGAACAGUCUGACUCUUUUGUUAGGGGAUAAUGCAGCAAGCAAUUUUAAGUUGAAGCCAAUACACAUUUACCAUAGUGAAAAUCCUAGGGCCCUUAAGAAUUAUGCUAAAUUUACUCUGCCUACAUGUAAAUGGAACAAUAAAACCUGGAUAGCAGCACGUCUGUUUACAGCAUCAUUUAUUGAAUAUUUUAAUACCACUGUUGGGACCUACUGCUCUGAAAAAAGAUUCCUUUCAAAAUGUUACUGCUCAUUGUCAAUGUACCUGGUCACCCAAGAGCUCUAGUGGAGAUGUACAAGGAGAUUAAUGUUGUUUUCAUGACUGCUUAUACAGCAUCCUUUCUGCAGCCCAUGGAUUAAGGAGUAAUUUUGACUUUCAAAGCCUAUUAUUUAACAAAUACAUUUUGGAAGGCUGUAGUUUCCAUAGAUAGUUAUCUCUGUGAUGGAUCUGGGUUAAAUAAAUAGAAAACCUGGAAAGGAUUCAGUACUCUAGGUGCCAUUAAGAACAUUUGUGGUUCAUAGAAGAAGGUCAGAAUAUCCACAUUAAUGGGAUUUUGGAAGAAGUUAUUCCAACCCUCAUGGAUGACUUUGAGGGGUUCAGGAUUUCAGUGGAGGAAGUAACUGAUGUGAUAGAAAUAGCAAGAGAACUAGAAGUGGAAUCUGAAGAUACAACAGAAUUGCUUCAAUCUCAUAAUAAAACUUGAAAGGAUGGCCAGGUGUGGUGGCUCACACCUCUAAUCCCAGCACUUUGGGAGGCUGAGGCGGGCAGAUCACGAGGUCAGGAGAUCGAGACCAUCCUGGCCAACAUGGUGAAACCCCAUCUCUACUAAAAUACAAAAAAUUAGCCGGGUGUGGUGGCAUGCGCCUGUAGUCCCAGCUACUUGGGAGGCUGAGACAGGGGAAUCGCUUGAACCUGGGAGGCAGAGGUUGCAGUGAGCCGAGAUCACAUCAUUGCACUCCAGCCUGGCAACAGAGCAAGACUCCAUCACACACACACACACACAUACACACACACACACACACACACACACACACACACACACACACAAACUUGAAAGGAUGAAGAGUUGCCUCUUAUGCAUGAGCAAAGAAAGUGAUUUCUUCAGAUAGAAUCUACUCUUGGUGAAGAUGAUGUGAACAUUGUUAAAUGACAACAAAGGAUUUACAAUAUUACAUAAACUUGGUUGAUGUGACAAGAUUUGAGAGGAUUGAUUGACUCCAAGUUUGAAAGUUCUAUUGUGUAAAAUGCCAUCAAACAGCAUAGUAUGGCACAGAGAACUCUUUUUGUGAAAGGAAGAGUUAAUCACUAUGGCAAACUUCAGUGCUGUCUUAUUUUAAUACAUUGCCACAGCCACCCCAGCCUUCAGCAACCACUGCCCUGUUUGUUCAGCAGCCAUUAACAUGGAGGCAAGACCCUCAACCAGCAAAAGGAUGAACAUUUUUUAGCAAUAAAGUAUUUUAAAAACCAAGGUAUGUCCAUUGAUUUUUUUUUUAGACGUAAUGUCAUUGGAUACUUGAGAGACUACACAGUAUAGUGUAAACAUAACUUCUAUGUGCACUGGGAAACCAAAAUGUUCACGUGACCCACUUUAUUGCCUGUUAGCUUUAUUGCUGUGGUCUGGAACUGAAUGUGAAGUGUCUUUGAGGGUACACUGCUAUGUAUUCUUUCCCUUUUAACUCUCAUUUAUUCCUAGUUCUGCAAGUAAAUCCAUAUUGAGUGCUCACUACCUCUUUUUAGGUCACUGGCUUUAUAGUCAUUCUUCUUGUCCAGAGCUUGUUCUGUAGUAAAUUCCUCAGGAAGAGCUCAUGGAACAAUAAUCUCUGAAUUGUUUCAUGUUGCAAACAGUUUGUCUGUGACCUUUGUACUUGAAAAUUUGUCUGGAUGUAAAAUCCUAGGUUCACAUUUUCUCUUCUUGAAUAUCUUAAAUAUGUUACUCUAUUGUUUUCUGACACUGAGGGUUGUUAACAAAGUCUGUGGCUAAUCUCUUUUGCUUUUCCCUUUUAAAUGACUUGGUCUUUUGUGUAUCCAAAGGAUUUUUUUUUCACAUUAAAAAAAAAUUCUAGGCUGGGCGCAGUGGCUCAUACCUAUAAUCCCAGCACUUUGGGAGGCUGAGGUGGGCAGAUCACUUGAGGUCAGGAGUUUGAGACCAGCCUGGCCAACAUGAUGAAACCCUGUCUCUACUAAAAAUACAAAAAUUAGUCAGGUGUGGUGGCAUGUGCAUGUGGUCCCACCUGCUCAGGAGGCUGAUACAGGAGAACGUGGGAGGUAGAGGUUGCAGUGAACUGAUUGUGCUGCUGCACUCCAGCCUGGGCAACAGAGCGAGACUCUAUCAAAAAUAAAAAAUACUCUGUUUUGUUUGAAUAUAUGAAAUUGUAUAUUUGUAUAUAAUUUGUAUAUUUACUUUCAUGUUUUAUCUGUUGUGUUUAUUUGCCCUUGUACUUUUUAUGGUUUCAUAUUCAAUUUUGAAAUUAUUUUUCUUUCUAAAUUUCUAAUAUUUUAUCACCACAUUUGUAAGUUUAAAAAAUAUUAUUUUAUGCUGUGAGUUUAUGUCUAGCAUUGGCUUCUUGUACUUCAUUUAGAGACAAACUCUCACUGUGUUCCCCAGGUUGGAAUGCAGUGGCUAUUCACAGGUGCAAUCACAGCUUCCUGCAGCCUUGAACUCCUGGCCUCAAGUGAUUCUCUAGCCUCAGCCUCCCAAGUAGCUGGGAUUGCAGGCACACACCACUGUGCCUGGCUAGCAUUGCUUCUUAAUUUUUUCUGGAUUAUUUUGACAUCAUAGGUUAUAGUUUUUAUAUCUUGUAGGAAUGUGUUUCUCACAUGCUUUCAUUGUCUGUAGGGAUAUUUUUAUUCUUGUAUUUUUUCUUAUAAUGUUGUAAAAGAUUUAACUUUGAUACUAUCCCAUUGUUUGCUUUUCUUUUUUUGUCUGAAAUUAAUUUUUUCAACUUUUAGAAGAGGAAGUUUGAUUUAGGAUAACUUUUCUAAUUUAUGCUCUACAGCACCCUCUUCUGUUGUUUUCAAGUAGUGUUUGAAAAUACUGUUUACUAUCUGAGAUCUCUAGGCUGUUUCUUUCUUACCCUUUGUUCCUAUGGUCUCACAUAGUAUUCUGUUCCUUGCAGUUUCUCUUCGCAGGAGGCUCUGUUCUGAAAGGGAGCUUUAACUGGUUAAUUUUGAGUCUUCAAGGGUCCAGGCUGCUCCAAGCCCAAUAGACAUUACCUUGAACUCCUUGCACUUGCUUACAGUGCUGUUUACUGGACUGUGUGGAAUGCCUCCCAGUUCAGCUGCUGCUCUCAAAUUGGUCCUUUAAGUUUUCCAGUGAGUUCUUUUAGUGAUGUAGGGAUCUUCCCGAGGUGGAUAAGAUACCCUAUUACUUCACUCUGCUACCUUUCGGGUUUUGUAGCUGUUGGUAGGUUGUUACCUCCUAUUCAUAUUUUGGGAUUUGUAGAAAUACUUUGUCAUCUAGUUUUCUAGUUUCGUUGUAUGUGUUGUCCAUGGGUUUUGGGUUUUGCUAUCCUAGUUGCUCAGUCAGGUUUUUUCUUGGGAGGUGGAGGAUGGGUUCAAGGAGCUUCAAAAUAAUCCCAUUUAUCUCAAAUCACUAGAAUAAAGAUAGAAUUUUUAAUAAAUGCCAGUAGAAUAAUUGGUUAGCCAUUGGAAAUGCGAUAAAAUGAGAUCUACAUCUCAUACCAUAUGUAAGGAUAAAUCCAUUAAAGUAUACAAGUGCCAGAGAAAAACAUGGGUGGAUUCCUCUAUAACCUGGGUGUAGGGAAAGCUUUUGUAAGUGUGAUUCAAAAAUCCAGAUGCAACAAAAGAAAAUAUUGAUACAUUUGACUAUAUAAAAUUAAAAAGCUUCUGUGUGGUAAAAACCCACCAUAACAAAAGACAAAUGACAAACUUAUAGAACAUAUCUGUAAUAUAUAUCACAGAUAUAGGGCUAAUAAGUAUAUAGAUGAUUCUUAAACAUGUGAUUAACCUCACUUAAAAUAUGAGAAAUGCAAAUUUAAUCUAUACUAAGAUACUGUUUCACAUACUACUUUGGCAAAAACUUAAAAAUGCAACAAUAUACUUUAUUGGUGAGGCUGUGAAGAAACUGGAACUCUCUUAAAAUCCUAGUGGUAAUGCAGAGGUGCAGCCUUUGUGGAGGGGAAUUUGAUUAUAGCUAACAAAACUGCGUAUGCAUUUAUGUAUUGACUCAGUAGUCCCACUGAGGAUACAGCUCUGAAAGUGUUCAAAUACAGAUGUGUAGGGUUAUUCAUUGGGCAUUUCUUGUUAUUACAAACUAUUGGAGACAACCUAAAUGCCCAUACAUGCAUAAGAGGUGGUUGAAUAAACUAUGGUACUUACACACAAUGGAGUGUUACAGAGCUGUGAAGAAAAAUGAAGGUGCUUUCUAUGGACUGAUAGAAAGUGAUUUCUAGGAAACAUUAAGUGAAAAGUACAAAAGACUAGAUAUGCUAUCUUUUAUGUAAGAAAGAAGGGAAAAUCAAAUAUGUUAUUUGCUCAUUUUGUACAAAAAGAAGAUGGAUAAAUAAGGAAAUGAUGAAACUGGUUACUUAGAGGGUAUGAGUAAGAACGGGGUCAAAAGGAGGGGGUGGUUGAACAAGGUAAGAGGAUAUUAUUGGGAUAAUCAGAGAAAUUGGAAUAAGGUCUGAUUAGUUUUAGUAUUCUAUCCAUGUUAAUUUCAUGAUUUUGAUAAUUGUACUAUAGUUAUAUAAGAGAAAGUCUUUGUUUUUAGAAUGUAAACACUGAAAUAUUUAGAAGUAACAAUCUCAGAUGGCUUAGGAAAAAAUGCAUGUGUGUGUAUAUAUAGAGAAGAAUAAAGCAAAUUUGUUAGAACAUUAAUUGGGAAAUCUAGAUGGAAGGCAUAGAGAAUUCAGUGUAUUAUUCUAGCAGAUUUUCAGUAUGUUUGCAAUCAUAUCAGAAUUAAAAGUUUAUUUUAAAAAUACUGUGCAAUUGCUAUAAGCCGUUUUCCCAGAAUUCCGUCUGUAAGAUGACUUAUGUGGCUCUUCUGCCUUUUUUCUAAAGGACUUCCAUAUUUUUAUGGAACACUAUUUUAUAGUUGCUGUGGAGGAACCCAAUUUUAUGAGUGUAGUGAAUCUUAUAAACAAGUUAUGCAAUGUGCUUUAGUUAUCAACUUUUGCAUUGGUAUUAUAUAUAAUUUUUAAAAUAGUCUUUACAUUAAAAAAAUGGUUUAAAUAUAUUUAGGAGGUAUAAGUGCAGAUUUCUUACAUGCAUAUAUUAGACAGCAGUGAAGUCUGGGCUUUUAGUGUACCCAUCACCUGAAUAGUGAAUGUUCUACCCAAUAGGUAAUUUUGCAACCCUCACCCCGCCACCCUCCCACCUUUUGUAAUCUGCAGUGUCUGUUAUUCCACUCUGUAUGUCUAUGUGUACACAUCGUUAAGCUCCCACUUAUAAGUGAGAACAUUUGAUAUUUGACUUUGUUUCAAAGUUAUUUCUUGGGAUAAUAGCCUCCAGUUCUGUCCAUGUUGCUGUGAAAGACAUGAUUUCAUUCUUUUUUAUGGCUGAGUAGUAUUCCAUGGUAUAUAUGUACAUUUUUCUUAUCCAGUCCUCCAUUGAUAGGCACUUAGGUUGAUUCCAUAUCUUUACUGUUGUGAAUAGUGCUAUGAUAAACAUACCAGUGCAGGUAUCUUUUAUAUAUAUAUAUUUUCUUUCCCUUUGGAUGUAUACCCAAUAGGGGGAUUGCUGGAUGGAAUGGUAGUUCUGUUUUUAGUUCUUUGAGAAAUCACCAUACUGUUUUCCAUAAAGAUGGUAAUAAUUUAUAUUCUCACCACAGUGUGUAAGCAUUCCUUUUUCUCCACAUCCUUGCCAACAUCUGUUGUUUUUUGACUUUUUAAUAAUAGCCAUUUUGACUGGUAUAGGAUGGUAAUCUCCUUGUGGUUUUAGUUUGCAUUUCUCUGAUGAUUAGUGAUGUUGAGCAUUUUUUCAUGUUUUUGGCCCCUUUGUAUGUCUUCUUUUGAAAAAUGUCUGUUCAUGUUGUUUGCCCACUUUUUAAUAGGGUUACUUGUUUUUUUCUUGUUGAGCUGAGUUCCUUGUGUAUUCUGGAUAUUAGCCCUUUAUUGGAUGCAUAGUUUGCAAAUAUUUUUUGCCAUUCUGUAGGUUGUCUGUUUACUCCAUAGACUGUUCCUUUGUUGUGUAGAAGCUUUUUAGUUUAAGUCUCAUUUGUCUAUUUUUGUUUUUGUUGUGCUUGGUUUUGGGACUUGGUCAUAAAUUCUUUGCCUAGGCCAAUGGCUAGAAGAGCUUUUCUCUUGUUUUAUAAACAAGUUAUAAGAUGUGCUUAUCAGCUUCUGGGAUUUGUGUAGUUUUAGGUCUUACGAUAAGGUCAUUAAUCCAUCUUGAGUUAAUUUUUGUAUGUGGUGAGAGGUAGGGGUCCAGUUUCAUUCUACAUGGCUAUGUAAUUUUCCCAGCACUGUUUAUUGAAUGGGGUGUCCUUUCCCCAGUGCAUAUUUUUGUUGACUUUGUAGACAUCAGUAGGUUGUAGGUGUGUGAUGUUAUUUCAGGGUUCUGUAUUGUGUUUGUAUAGAAAUUUUAGAAUUCACAUGUUGGGAUUUUGGUGGAGAUUGCUUCUGAUAGAUAGAUCACUUUCUAAUAUUGGUUAUAUUGCCGUAUUUUUUUGGAUCAGUCUUGCCAUGAGCUUAUAAAAUGUGUUAAUUUUUCCCAAAAUUAAACUUUUAGUGUAGUUUUCUCUCAUGUCUUUUUUAUUUCAUUAUUUUUUGCUUCUAUCUGUGUUUUUAUAUUUUUCGGCUGGGCACAGUGGCUCAUGCCUGUAAUCCCAGCACUUUGGGAUGUUGAGGCAGGCAGACCAUGAGGUCAAGAGAUCAAGACCAUCCUGGCCAACAUGGUGAAACCUCGUCUCUCCUAAAAAUACAAAAAUUAGCUGGGCAUGGUGGUGUGCGCCUGUAGUCCAAGCUACUUAGGAGGCUGAGGCAGGAGAAUUGCUUGAACCUGGGAGGCGGAGGUUGCAUUGAGCCAGGAUUGUGCCACUGUACUCUAGCCGGGGGGGCAGAGCGAGACUCCAUCUCAAAAAAAAAAAAAAAAAAAAAUGGAGUCCCACUGUGUUGUCCGGGCUGGUCUCAAACUCCUGGACUCAAGCAGUUCUUCUGCCUUGGCCUCCUAAAGUGCUGUGAUUACAGGUGUGAGCCACUGCACCUGGCCAUUUUUAUUUAUUUUAAAUUAUUUUAGGCACUGGACAACAUGUUGAACCUUCUUCUUAAAUAUACGCAUUUAAGGUUAUAAAGUUCUUUGUGAACACUGCUUUAGUUGGAGCCUACAGAUUUUUUGUUAUAAACCUUUUCAUUUUGUAAGUCUGUUGUUACAUAUAUUACUCAUUUCAAAAUAUUUUCUGAUUUCUUUGACCCAUGACUUUUCACCACCCCAAAGUUCAGUGGUUUCAGCGAUUAUCUUUUACCCUCAGUUCUGUGGGUGGCUGGGCAGUUCCUCUGCUGGUUUUGUCUAGGUUCACUUGUAAGACUGUUGAUUUCUUUUUUCCAUUAUUUCAUUUUUUGUUGGGAACAGGCCCCUAAAACUGGCCAUAAACAAAAUCUCUGCAGCACUGUGAGAUGUUUGCAAUGGCCACGAUGCCCAUGCUGAAGGUUGCAGGUUUACCGGAAUGAGGGCAAGGGACACCUGGCCCACCCAGGUUGGAAAACUGCUUAAGGCUUUCUUAAACCACAAACAAUAGCAUGAGCAAUCUGUGCCUUAAGGACAUGUUCCUGCUGCAGAUAACUAGCCAGACCCAUCCCCUUGUUUUGGCCCAUCCCUUUAUUUCCCGUAAGAAAUGCUUUUAGUUAAUCUCUAAUCUAUAGAAACAAUGCUUAUACUGGCUUGCUAUCAAUAAAUAUGUGGGUAAAUCUCUGUUUGGGGCUCUCAGCUCUGAAGGCUGUGAGACCCCUGAUUGCCCACUCCACACUCUAUAUUUCUGUGUGUGUGUGUCUUUAAUUCCUCUAGCGCCACUGGGUUAAGGUCUCCACGACCAAGGUGGUCUUGGCAAGUGGCGCCCAUACAUGGGGCUCAAACCCAGGUUGAGGGGUCGCUGGAGUGAUGGUUGGAGAACAUGGAACUAAGCAGGAGGACACCCGGGUACUCUAAGCAGUCCCCAUGGUGGGUAAGAAGGGGAGCUCGGAAGCAUCAGGGUAACAUUGGGACAAGUGUGGGCUCUGGUUCGUUCCACCUUGGAACCUUUUCACACUGAUGUGGAAGGAGAGUAUAACGAAGUAACAGAGCAGGUUUGUUUGCCACCUAAAGUAAAAACAGCAAAGGAGGAAGAGGUUCAUCCCUACCCUCCUGCACCCCCUCCUUAUUUUGAAGAAAAGGAGUGGCCUGACCCUCCAGAUCUUUCUUUUCCAGAGGACACUGGGCGAAAAGUAGUUGCCCCAGUGACUGUUCGAGCAGUGCCUCUUCAGUGCUGUAAAACAGGGACCAAAAGAACUGUACAUGGAUUUUAUAGCUCGGUUACAGGAGUCUCUUAAAAAGGUGAUUGCAGAUUCAGCUGCUCAGGAUAUAGCGUUGCGGUUAUUAGCUUUCGGCAAUGCUAAUCCCGAGUGCCAGGCUGCUCUGCGACCUAUUAGAGGGAAAGUACAUUUAGUUGAUUAUAUCAAGGCCUGUGAUGGUAUCGUAGGUAAUCUGCCUAAGGCUACUCUGCUAGCCCAAGCAAUGGCAGGACUGAGAGUGGGUAAAGGAAAUACUCAGUUUCCUGGAGCUUGUUCUAACUGUGGGAAGCAUGGUCAUACUAAAAAAGAAUGUAGAAAAAAUCAGCGAAUCAGGCUGCCAGAUAGGGGAAAAAAGAAAACUGCUGAGCCUGAAAUAUGUCCAAAAUGUGAAAAAGGAAAACAUUGGGCUAAUUGGUGUCACUCUAACUUUGAUAAAGAUGGGAACCCAAUUUCGGGCCCCAUUCCAAAUGGGAGCAUUUCCGGCUCAGGCCAUUCCCUCACCCCUGGGCAAUGUCUGUCCCCUGCCACAGCUGGUAGUGCCGUGGUAGAUUUAUGCUGCACAAAAGCUGUGAGCCUUCUGCCUGGGGAACCCCUGCAAAAGGUCCCAACAGGAGUCUGUGGACCCUUGCCAGCGGGGACAAUAGGAUUACUUCUAGGAAGGUCUAAUUUAAAUUUAAAAGGAGUACAAAUACAUACAGGAGUCAUUGAUUCAGAUUACAAUGGAGAAAUUCAAAUUGUUACAUCUACUUCUGUUCCCUGGAAAGCAGAGCCAGGAGAGCGCAUAGCACAGCUCCUGAUUGUGCCGUAUGUGGAAAUGGGGAAAAGUGAAAUUAAACAGGAGGAUUUGGAAGCACAAAUAGACAAGGCAAAGCAGCUUAUUGGGUGAAUCAAAUUACUGAUAAAUGUCCUACCUGUGAAAUAACUAUUCAGGGAAAGAAAUUUAAGGGUUGGGUAGAUACAGGAGCGGACAUUUCAAUCAUUUCUCUACAGCACUGGCUGUCUGCGUGGCCAAUUCAACCUGUUCAAUUUAACAUAGUUGGAGUUGGUAAAGCCCCUGAAGUAUAUCAAAGUAGUUAUAUUUUGCAUUAUGAAGGACCUGAUGGACAACCUGGGACUAUUCAACCGAUUGUAACUUCUGUACCUAUAAAUCUGUGGGGAAGAGAUUUAUUACAAUAAUGGGGAGCAAAAGUUCUAAUUCCAGAGCAAUUAAACAGCCCUUAGAGUCAACAUAUGAUGCCUGAAAUCAGGUAUGUCCCUGGUAUGGGACUAGGAAAAAAUUUGCAAGAUUUGAAGGAACCGCUUUAAGCGGAAAGACAAAGUUCCUGCCAAGGUUUAGGAUAUCAUUUUUGAUGGCAGCCAUUGUUCAGCCUCUAGAACCUAUACCUUUAAAAUGGUUAACAGAUAAGCCAAUUUGGAUAGAACAAUGGCCACUAAGUAAAGAGAAACUGGAGGCUUUAGAGAACGUCGUUAAUAAACAAUUAGAAGGACACAUAGCUCCAACAUUUUCUCCUUGGAAUUCACCAGUUUUUGUAAUUAAGAAAAAAUCAGGUAAAUAGAGAAUGUUAACUGAUUUAAGAGCCAUUAAUUCAGUUAUACAACCUAUGGGAGCAUGGGAGCAUUGCAGCCAGGAUUGCCUUCUCCUGCUAUGAUUAAAAAAAAUUGGCCUUUAAUAGUCAUAGAUUUAAAAGACUGUUUCUUUACUAUCCCCUUAGCUGAGCAGGACUGUGAAUGGUUUGCAUUUACAAUUCCUGCAGUAAACAACCUACAGCCUGCUAAGUGUUUUCAUUGGAAAGUGUUGCCACAGGGCAUGUUAAACAGUCCAAUAAUUUGCCAGACUUAUGUAGAGCAAGCAAUUAAACCUAUUGAUAAAAAAUUUUCACAGUGUUACAUUAUUCAUUAUAUGGACAAUAUAAUUUGUGCUGCCCCCUAUCGAGAAACAUUACCCCAAUGUUAUGAUCACUUGCAAAAUUCAGUUUCUAGUGCUGGUUUAAUUAUAGCUCCUGACAAAAUUCAGACUACUACUUCUUACUCCUACUUAGGGACCUUAGUAAAUGACAUUACCAUUGUGCCACAGAAAGUAGCCAUACGUAGGGAUCAAUUGAAAACAUUAAAUGACUUUCAAAAAUUACUAAGGGACAUUAAUUGGAUACGACCUGCUCUAGGCAUUCCUACCUAUGCCAUGAGUAAUCUAUUUUCUAUCCUUAGAGGAGAUCCUAGUCUCACUAGCCCUUGGCAAUUAACAAAAGAAGCUGAGGCAGAGCUUCAGCUAAUCAAAAGCAAGUCCAUAAAGCUCAAAUAAAUAGAAUAGAUCCAGAAAAGACUCUAGAUUUGCCAGUUUUUCCAACUCAGCAUUCAUCUACUGGUGUUAUUGUCCACAAGCAGGACUUAGUAGAGUGGCUUUUUCUUCCACAUACUAAUUGACGGACUCUAACUCCUUAUUUGGAUCAAAUUGCUACUAUGAUAGGAAACGGGAGAACUCGGAUUGUUAGAUUACAUGGAUAUGAUCCUGGAAAAAUUGUUGUCUCUCUCAUGAAGGCACAAGUACAGCAAGCUUUUAUAAAUAGUCUUACUUGGCAAACCCAUUUAGCUCACUUUGUGGGUAUUCUCGAUAAUCAUUUUCCUAAAACGAAACUGUUUCAAUUUUUGAAAUGAACUAAUUGGAUCCUCCCUAGAAUAACUAAAUUUAAACCAAUUGAAGUUGCUGAGAAUGUUUUUACAGAUGGGUCUAGUAACGGUAAAGCUUCUUAUUUUGGAUCAAAAGGUAAAGUUUUCCAGACGCCUUAUACUUCAGCUCAAAAAGCGGAGCUUUUGUAGCUGUAAUUGAGGUAUUGACUGCUUUUAAUAUGCCUAUUAAUGUGAUUUCUGAUUCUUCAUAUGUGGUUCAUUCCACACAAAUAAUUGAAAAUGCUCAGUUAUGUUUUCUUCUGCCUGUGUUAAACGUCACCUUUUGCAGUGUUUUGCGGUGAUGGGCAUUCCAGCUUCUAUUAAAACAGAUAAUGCCCCAGGCUAUACUAGCCAAGCUCUAGCUGCAUUUUUCUCUAUGUGGAAUAUUAAACACAGUACUGGUAUCCCAUAUAAUUCUCAAGGACAAGCCAUAGUGGAAAAAAUGAAUCUGUCCCUGAAACAGCAGUUGCAAAAGCAGAGGGGGAUAAACAGGGACUACGGGACACCCCAUAUGCAAUUGAAUCUAGCAUUAUUAACUUUAAAUUUUUUUUAGCAUGCCUAAAGGCUAGAUGCUAUCAGCGGCUGAACAGCAUCUACAGAAACCAGCUGCAAAGACAGAAGCAGAACAACUGGUUUGGUGGAGAGAUCUGAUAACAAAAAGUUGGGAAAUAGGUAAAAUAAUAACUUGGGGUAGAGGUUAUGCUUGUGUUUCUCCAGGACCGAAUCAACAGCUGAUUUGGAUACCAUUAAGACACCUGAAACCUUAUUAUGAGCCAGAUGCCAAGGAAGAGAUUCUGGGAGGAUCCCGAGGACCCCGUAGUUGCAGCCAUGUCGAGAUUGACACUGAGGAGGAUCCCAACUGUCAUGAGCAAUACCCAUCGAACAUAGCCACCUACUUGGGGACAGAUCAAGAAGCUGUCACAGAUGGCGGAAUAAAAACCUGAGGAAAGCAGGACAACCAGUCACAAUGAGUAAUUUGAUGGUACCUAUGAUAGCAGUGAUUACCAUUGCCGUAUUUCAUGGAAACUUGGAGAGAGAAAAGUGAUGAAGUGAUGGGAGAGCUGACUGAUCAUGUGACUCAUUGUAAGAAAAGUGGAAAACCACCAUUACAGAACAAUGAGAAAGAGGGGAAAAAGGAGCGAGCUGUGGUGGACAAGGUGUUUUUCUCAAGGCUCAUACAGAUUCUGAAAAUCAUGGUCCCUAGAACAUUUUGUAAAGAGACAGGUUACUUGGUACUUAUUGCUGUUAUGCUGGUGUCUCGAACAUAUUGUGAUGUUUGGAUGAUUCAAAAUGGGACACUAAUUGAAAGUGGUAUCAUUGGUCGUAGCAGGAAAGAUUUCAAGAGAUACUUACUCAACUUCAUCGCUGCCAUGCCUCUUAUCUCUCUGGUUAAUAACUUCUUGAAGUAUGGGUUAAAUGAGCUUAAACUGUGCUUCCGAGUAAGGCUCACUAAAUACCUCUAUGAGGAGUAUCUUCAAGCUUUCACAUAUUAUAAAAUGGGGAAUCUGGACAACAGAAUAGCUAAUCCAGACCAGCUGCUUACACAAGAUGUAGAAAAAUUUUGUAACAGUGUAGUCGAUCUGUAUUCAAAUCUUAGUAAGCCAUUUUUAGACAUAGUUUUGUAUAUCUUUAAGUUAACGAGUGCAAUUGGAGCUCAGGGCCCAGCGAGCAUGAUGGCCUACUUGGUUGUUUCUGGGCUAUUCCUAACUCGACUUCGAAGACCCAUUGGUAAGAUGACAAUAACUGAGCAAAAGUAUGAAGGAGAAUAUAGAUAUGUUAAUUCUCGGCUCAUCACAAACAGUGAAGAAAUUGCCUUUUACAAUGGGAAUAAAAGAGAAAAGCAGACAGUCCACUCAGUCUUCCGAAAACUGGUGGAACACCUACAUAAUUUCAUUUUGUUUCGGUUUUCAAUGGGCUUCAUUGAUAGUAUUAUUGCCAAAUACCUUGCCACUGUUGUUGGUUACCUAGUUGUCAGUCGCCCUUUCUUAGAUUUGUCUCAUCCUCGACAUCUCAAGAGUACACAUUCGGAACUUCUAGAGGAUUACUACCAAAGUGGAAGAAUGCUUUUGCGAAUGUCUCAAGCUCUGGGUCGAAUAGUUUUGGCUGGGCGUGAAAUGACUAGAUUGGCCGGUUUUACUGCUCGGAUUACAGAAUUAAUGCAAGUACUGAAGGAUUUAAAUCAUGGCAAAUAUGAGCGCACAAUGGUCUCACAACAGGAAAAGGGUAUUGAAGGAGUACAAGUCAUUCCCUUGAUACCUGGUGCUGGAGAAAUCAUUAUUGCAGAUAACAUUAUAAAGUUUGAUCAUGUUCCUUUAGCAACGCCAAAUGGAGAUGUUUUGAUCCGAGACCUUAAUUUUGAAGUUCGAUCUGGGGCUAAUGUUCUAAUUUGUGGUCCAAAUGGCUGCGGAAAGAGUUCACUUUUCCGUGUUCUUGGUGAAUUAUGGCCUCUUUUUGGAGGACGUCUAACUAAACCUGAAAGAGGAAAAUUAUUUUAUGUUCCUCAGAGACCUUACAUGACCCUUGGAACACUUCGAGAUCAAGUGAUAUAUCCAGAUGGACGAGAAGAUCAGAAAAGGAAGGGAAUUUCUGACCUAGUACUGAAGGAAUACUUAGACAAUGUCCAGUUGGGUCAUAUCCUUGAACGUGAAGGAGGCUGGGACAGUGUUCAGGAUUGGAUGGACGUACUCAGUGGUGGAGAAAAGCAAAGAAUGGCGAUGGCAAGAUUAUUUUAUCAUAAACCCCAGUUUGCCAUUUUGGAUGAAUGCACAAGUGCAGUUAGUGUCGACGUGGAAGGCUACAUUUAUAGUCAUUGUCGAAAGGUUGGCAUCACUCUCUUCACUGUGUCUCAUAGGAAAUCUCUUUGGAAACAUCAUGAGUACUACCUGCAUAUGGAUGGCAGAGGCAACUAUGAAUUCAAACAGAUAACAGAAGAUACAGUUGAGUUUGGCUCUUAGAGAAAUCUGGAGAACUAUACCUGCUUCAGUGAAAUAAUUACAGAAUAUACUUAGAAAGGCAAAGUACAUUGUAAAAUAAAGUUGAGCUUAGUUUUUUUUAAAAAAAAAAACAAAGCAACAAAUUAACUAGAUACAGAAUAAUGGAGAACAAGUUGUUAAAACAUUUAAUAUUAUAUAGGAUAUUGCUAAUUGUGUAUAUGUUGGUUUAAUUAAUAAUAUGUACUAAGAAUGUCCUUAUUCUUGUGGUUAAAAACCUGCCUAAAUUAAAUUGGGCUUCAAUCACUGUAACCUGAUUCAUCCUGGGAUGUAAACCAUUCGAAGUCAGCUAAUUGGACUUUUAUGGCUCUAUCUUUUCCUUCAGUGAAGAACCCUAUUUAAAACUGGGUCAUCAUUUGUCCUGUUCUAGCAAGAUAGUCUUCAGUUUCAUUUUCCUGUGCCCUGUGGUAGUUGGAAACAAAUCAUAAUGUAUUAUUUAAAUGUUUAACAUCAUUGCAUAACAGCGUUUAUUAUACAGUGGCAGAUUUCUUUAGCUGCCACAGUAAUACUCAUUCCUUGUGUGUGUCUUGGAGUGCAUUUGACUCCAGGAAAAGCCAUUUUGGUUUUCCUUAACUAAAUGAUAAAUGUACCCCUCUCAGUCUGCAGUAUUGAGUUGUUUAAAGUAUAUGUGCAGUCUUGCUUACAAGGAGGGGUUACCAUGUAUCACACCUAAUCUUCCCAAUGUUUGGGAUAUUAAAACACAAAGUCCUUAACAUGCCAGGCUCAAGGUCUUAUAAGAGUUCUAGAUUUUUAAGAGAAUUAGACAAAUUUGUGUGUGUUAGAAGCCCAUUCAUUAGAAGUGUGGUGGUUAUUUGGUAUUAAACUCCAAAUGAGCCAUAGGAAGGCACUACAUGAAAUAAUGCACUGAGUAUGCAAUGCUAUCACUGUCUUUGACUGUGAUUUUAUGUUUAAAAAGUAUGUUCUAAAAUUAUUAUAUAUACAUGGGUGAAUUAUGUUUCCGAGGCACUGUUUUAUCUCUGUGAAUCUUGAAUAACUUUUUUAUAUUUGGGUUAUGAUGUCAAACGAUCCUAAGCGAAGAUGAUUUCAGUUCAUCAAAUCAUCAUUAAUGACUUUAUGUAUUAUUUGCACAGGGAGAAUUGAAACUGAGUAUAAUCAAUAAGCUAGAUACGAAAUCAGUUUCUCAAACUGAGCUUCAGAAAGGGGCAUUUUGUACUCUUGUUUUUGCAUAACUGGUUUUGUUUUUUUGCAGAAUUAACUAUAACAAUCACUGGCUACCGAAGUAAACUGAUGUACUGAAUUCCAUAAUACAUAACAUUCAAUUUUUACCACUUCUGUUUAGCGAACUUGUAUACUUAUUUUCUGUUCAGAUUAAAAAAAAAAAAAAAAAACUCAGAUAUCCUAUACAACCUUUGCUUGUUCUUUUUAUUCUGGUAUCUAAAUACUGAGAAGUUCAUUUAUAAUUCAGCCUUGACUUGAAAACAUAGAUAGUUUAAUCUUGACUUGAAAAACACAAAAAUAAAUUCAGAAAAUGCUUUUA